GCACACAGGCAGUGGGUACGGCAGACUGGGGUUGGUGGCAUGGCCCAGGACCCCACGCUGACUAGUGAGCCCCUCCGCAGGCAUAGCGUGGCGUCAGCCCAGCUGCAGGAGAAGCUGGCAGGAGCCCAGCGCCAGCUGGGGCAGCUCCGGGCUCAGGAAGCCGGCCUGCAGCAGGAGCAGAGGAAGGCAGACACCCACAAGAAGAUGACUGAGUUCUAGAGACCCCACAAGCACUAUGGACGAAGCGUGGGACCCCAGCACGGGCUGCCCUCAGGAAGACCAGUGUUGCCCGAGGAGGGGCCGGCCUGCUGGCCUGGGGCGUGCAGACACUGCUGAGUGGAGACAGAGCUGCGGGGUCCCAUCUGGACACUUACUUGCCCACCUGCCAGUGUCUUGGGCAUUUCCUUGGCAAGGACAUUAAAGUGAUUUCAUCACAGUGUCAUUCAGUGGAGAUCAGCUGGCUGCAGGGUCUCUGGGGAGAGAAGGGGCCUCGGCUUCACAGGAUGGGGCUGCCAGUGUCCUGGGCCCCUCCUGCCCUCUGGGUUCUAGGGUGCUGCGCCCUGCUCCUCUCGCUGUGGGCGCUGUGCACAGCCUGCCGCAGGCCCGAGGACGCUGUAGCCCCCAGGAAGAGGGCGCGGAGGCAGCGGGCGAGGCUGCAGGGCAGUGCGACGGCGGCGGAAGCGCAAGUCGGACACCAGACUGCACGAGCUGCACCGGGGCCCGCGCAGCAGCAGGGCCCUGCGGCCUGCCAGCAUGGAUCUCCUGCGCCCACACUGGCUGGAGGUGUCCAGGGACAUCACCGGACCGCAGGCAGCCCCCUCUGCCUUCCCACACCAGGAGCUGCCCCGGGCUCUGCCGGCAGCUGCAGCCACCGCAGGGUGCGCUGGCCUCGAGGCCACCUAUUCCAACGUGGGGCUGGCGGCCCUUCCCGGGGUCAGCCUGGCGGCCAGCCCUGUGGUGGCCGAGUAUGCCCGCGUCCAGAAGCGCAAAGGGACCCAUCGCAGUCCCCAAGAGCCACAGCAGGGGAAGACUGAGGUGACCCCGGCCGCUCAGGUGGACGUCCUGUACUCCAGGGUCUGCAAGCCUAAAAGGAGGGACCCAGGACCCACCACAGACCCGCUGGACCCCAAGGGCCAGGGAGCGAUUCUGGCCCUGGCGGGUGACCUGGCCUACCAGACCCUCCCGCUCAGGGCCCUGGAUGUGGACAGCGGCCCCCUGGAAAACGUGUAUGAGAGCAUCCGGGAGCUGGGGGACCCUGCUGGCAGGAGCAGCACGUGCGGGGCUGGGACGCCCCCUGCUUCCAGCUGCCCCAGCCUAGGGAGGGGCUGGAGACCCCUCCCUGCCUCCCUGCCCUGAACACUCAAGGACCUGUGCUCCUUCCUCCAGAGUGAGGCCCGUCCCCCGCCCCGCCCCGCCUCACAGCUGACAGCGCCAGUCCCAGGUCCCCGGGCUGCCAGCCCGUGAGGUCCGUGAGGUCCUGGCCGCUCUGACAGCCGCGGCCUCCCCGGGCUCCAGAGAAGGCCCGCGUCUAAAUAAAGCGCCAGCGCAGGAUGAAAGCG